AGAGUCCGGCUCAGGCUCCGGCUGCGGCUCCAGCCCGCGAUGCCCCAUUCCGUGACCCUGCGCGGGCCUUCGCCCUGGGGCUUCCGCCUGGUGGGCGGCCGGGACUUCAGCGCGCCCCUCACCAUCUCACGGGUCCAUGCUGGCAGCAAGGCUGCAUUGGCUGCCCUGUGCCCAGGAGACCUGAUCCAGGCCAUCAAUGGUGAGAGCACAGAGCUCAUGACACACCUGGAGGCACAGAACCGCAUCAAGGGCUGCCACGAUCACCUCACACUGUCUGUGAGCAGGCCUGAGGGUAGGAGCUGGCCCAGUGCCCCUGAUGACAGCAAGGCUCAGGCACACAGGAUCCACAUCGAUCCUGAGAUCCAGGACGGCAGCCCAACAACCAGCAGGCGGCCCUCAGGCACCGGGACUGGGCCAGAAGAUGGCAGACCAAGCCUGGGAUCUCCAUAUGGACAACCCCCUCGCUUUCCAGUCCCUCACAAUGGCAGCAGCGAGGCCACCCUGCCAGCCCAGAUGAGCACCCUGCAUGUGUCUCCACCCCCCAGCGCUGACCCAGCCAGAGGCCUCCCGCGGAGCCGGGACUGCAGAGUCGACCUGGGCUCCGAGGUGUACAGGAUGCUGCGGGAGCCAGCCGAGCCCGUGGCCGCGGAGCCCAAGCAGUCAGGCUCCUUCCGCUACUUGCAGGGCAUGCUAGAGGCCGGCGAGGGCGGUAAGACGCCUGCCACCUGUCCCCAUCUGCCUUCCCACUCCCUGCAGUGCCCAGGUUGCCCCCUAGCGACCCCACGUCCCGCCUCGCAGUCACCUGCCCUCUUCGGUCUCUGCGGCCCGGUCCCACGCCCUUGCUACAACCUUGCUACGCCCUGGCUUCCCGAUUCCCUCUCCACCCCCUGUCGCUGCCCCUCACCCCACGCCCGCCAAACCCGUUCCCCAGUCUCGGGUGCCGAUGGCCCGUCUGGCGCCCAACCAAACACCCCGCAGAAAUGGAGUUCUGACCUCCUCACCCCGUUCAUGCCACCUACGCUCCGGGUUUCAGGGGAUUGGCCCGGGCCUGGCGGCCCCCGGAACCUCAAGCCCACGGCCAGCAAGCUGGGCGCUCCGCUGAGCGGCCUGCAGGGGCUGCCCGAGUGCACGCGCUGCGGCCACGGCAUCGUGGGCACCAUCGUCAAGGCACGGGACAAGCUCUACCAUCCCGAGUGCUUCAUGUGCAGUGACUGCGGCCUGAACCUCAAGCAGCGUGGUUACUUCUUUCUGGACGAGCGGCUCUACUGUGAGAGCCACGCCAAGGCGCGCGUGAAGCCGCCCGAGGGCUACGACGUGGUGGCGGUGUACCCCAAUGCCAAGGUGGAACUCGUCUGAGCUGGGACCCUGCUCCCACGCCUGCUUCUUAAGGUCCCUGCUCGGCCGGUGUAAAUAUGUUUCACCCUGUCCCUCUAAUAAAGCUCCUCUGCUCCACCUUGAACCUGUCACCUGGCCUGCCACCCUCCUGCGCAGGCCAUGCAUGGCUCCCGAGUACAGUAGUAUCUGCUUAGGUGCCAGGCAUGUCCUAGGCUCUGGGUGCAGUAGUGAGCAGGACGGGUACCAUGCUGCCCUGAAGGGGGCCACAGCCUGGGUGGAAGGCAGACCUGAAUCACAACGGGCCAGCUCUAGUAAUACGAAGGUGAGGUCUGGGAUGCUGCGUGCGGCGCGACGACAGGAGGUAUGACCUGGGUGGGGUCAGGGAAAGUCUUAGCUGAGAACUAAGAGAUGAGGGAGGCACAAACUCUGCACGGGGGAACUGUGUGUGCAAAGGUGAGCUGGGGGCGAGAAAGGCCUCUGUGGCCGUCAUCGGCACUAGCGGGUUGGGGGUGGUGGUGGGGUGCUGGCAGCCUCAGGAGCGAUCGCUCCCCUGGAGAGGGUGAUUGAGUGUGGAGAUCACCGGGGCCGCCGCGGGCCGUCUGCACUUCUGUUCCAGGUUUUUCUGGCAUUUUCUGUUCCAGGUUUCUUCCACCCACGAGCACUUUAUUCUCCUCCGAGACCCCCUUUUCUUCCCCUUCCUCUCUCCCCCACCAGGGGGCGCGCUUAAAUUUCCAGACAGAGACCAGAAGGAAGGUUUAGAAAGAAAAGAACACUUGCCCAGGGCAGCUUUGCCCUCCAAGAGGCUCCCUCCUGUCUCUAAGUCAAUUCCACCCCUCCUCGAAGUCCCGGCUUCCACCCCUCUCCUCAGAGUCCCGGCGUUUACCUCGUGGUGUGUUUGCCUUGGGCCUUUCAUGCCCCGGCUGCACACAUCGUCUGUGAAUUGUGGCUGUUCACUCCCGAGGAUGUGUCCUAGACUCCGGGUCGCGUGGAUCUACCCUCUAGUUUACUUGCUCGGGAGAAGAAACUGACUCGUUUUAUUUAGUGCCUAUUUAGCGAGCCCAGAGUAACGUACAUUUGUGCUGUUUUCAAUUUUGUGCUAUCGCAAAUCACAAAAAAACUGUUAUCAAUUCACAUUCAUCAUCAGCACGAGACCCAUUUCCUUGUGCUCCUGCCAGCUCAGGAUAUUAUGUUUCUUUUUUCAUUUUUGCCAGUCUGUUAAGUAAAAUGUCAUAUGCGUUUGUUUUAA